CAAACACUGCCUGGAGUGAGAGCAAACUACCAGCGCAGUGGGGCCGGCGCGAGUGUGCGUGUGUGUGCGUGUGUGUGUGCGAGCGCGGUGGAGGGGGGGGACCAACUGCUUCACACUUUCAACACUGCACUGAAGAGGGAGAGCGAGAGAGAGACUGGAGACGCACAGAUCCCCCCAAGGUCUCCCAAGCCUACCGUCCCACAGAUUAUUGUACAGAGCCCCAAAAAUCGAAACAGAGGAAACGAACAGCAGUUGAACAUGGACGAAGGAAUUCCUCAUUUGCAAGAGAGACAGUUACUGGAACAUAGAGAUUUUAUAGGACUGGACUAUUCCUCUUUGUAUAUGUGUAAACCCAAAAGGAGCAUGAAACGAGACGACACCAAGGAUACCUACAAAUUACCGCACAGAUUAAUAGAAAAGAAAAGAAGAGACCGAAUUAAUGAAUGCAUUGCUCAGCUGAAAGAUUUACUGCCUGAACAUCUGAAAUUGACAACUCUGGGACAUCUGGAGAAAGCUGUAGUCUUGGAAUUAACUUUGAAACACUUAAAAGCUUUAACCGCCUUAACCGAGCAACAGCAUCAGAAGAUAAUUGCUUUACAGAAUGGGGAGCGAUCUCUGAAAUCGCCCAUUCAGUCCGACUUGGAUGCGUUCCACUCGGGAUUUCAAACAUGCGCCAAAGAAGUCUUGCAAUACCUCUCCCGGUUUGAGAGCUGGACACCCAGGGAGCCGCGGUGUGUCCAGCUGAUCAACCACUUGCACGCCGUGGCCACCCAGUUCUUGCCCACCCCGCAGCUGUUGACUCAACAGGUCCCUCUGAGCAAAGGCACCGGCGCUCCCUCGGCCGCCGGGUCCGCGGCCGCCCCCUGCCUGGAGCGCGCGGGGCAGAAGCUGGAGCCCCUCGCCUACUGCGUGCCCGUCAUCCAGCGGACUCAGCCCAGCGCCGAGCUCGCCGCCGAGAACGACACGGACACCGACAGCGGCUACGGCGGCGAAGCCGAGGCCCGGCCGGACCGCGAGAAAGGCAAAGGCGCGGGGGCGAGCCGCGUCACCAUCAAGCAGGAGCCUCCCGGGGAGGACUCGCCGGCGCCCAAGAGGAUGAAGCUGGAUUCCCGCGGCGGCGGCAGCGGCGGCGGCCCGGGGGGCGGCGCGGCGGCGGCGGCAGCCGCGCUUCUGGGGCCCGACCCUGCCGCCGCGGCCGCGCUGCUGAGACCCGACGCCGCCCUGCUCAGCUCGCUGGUGGCGUUCGGCGGAGGCGGAGGCGCGCCCUUCCCGCAGCCCGCGGCCGCCGCGGCCCCCUUCUGCCUGCCCUUCUGCUUCCUCUCGCCUUCUGCAGCUGCCGCCUACGUGCAGCCCUUCCUGGACAAGAGCGGCCUGGAGAAGUAUCUGUACCCGGCGGCGGCUGCCGCCCCGUUCCCGCUGCUAUACCCCGGCAUCCCCGCCCCGGCGGCAGCCGCGGCAGCCGCCGCCGCCGCUGCCGCCGCCGCCGCCGCGUUCCCCUGCCUGUCCUCGGUGUUGUCGCCCCCUCCCGAGAAGGCGGGCGCCGCCGCCGCGACCCUCCUGCCGCACGAGGUGGCGCCCCUUGGGGCGCCGCACCCCCAGCACCCGCACGGCCGCACCCACCUGCCCUUCGCCGGGCCCCGCGAGCCGGGGAACCCGGAGAGCUCUGCUCAGGAAGAUCCCUCGCAGCCAGGAAAGGAAGCUCCCUGAAUCCUUGCGUCCCGAAGGACGGAGGUUCAAGCAGAGUGAGAAGUUAAAAUACCCUUAAGGAGGUUCAAGCAGAGUGAGAAGUUAAAAUACCCUUAAGGUCUUUAAGGGAGGAAGUGUAAUAGAUGCACGACAGGCAUAAACAAGAACAACAAAACAGGUGUUAUGUGUACAUUCGGAGUUCCUGUUUUGCUCAUCCCGCACCACCCCACCCUCCACACACUAACAUCCCUUUCUUCCCCCCACCAGCUGUAAAAGAUCCUAUGCGAAAGACACUGGCUCUUUUUUUUAAUCCCCCAAAUAAAUUUUGCCCCCUUUUAGGCCAUGUUCCAUUAUCUCUUAAAAUUGGAACCUAAUUCGAGAGGAAGUAAGAAGGGUCUGUUCUGUGGCUGAGCUAGGUGAACCCCGGGGUAGGGGAAAGAUGUUAACACCUUUGACGUCUUUGGAGUUGACAUGGAACAGCAGGUAGUUGUUAUGUAGAGCUAGUUCUCAAAGCUGCCCUGCCUGUUUUAGGAGGCGUUCCACAAACAGAUUGAGGCUCUUUUAGAAUUGAAUUUACUCUUCAGUAUUUUCUAAUGUUCAGCUUUCUAAAAGGCAUAUAUUUUUCAAAGAAGUGAGGAUGCAGUUUCUCACGUUGCAACCUAUUCUGAAGUGGUUUAAAUGGUAUCUCUUAGUAACUUGCACUCGUUAAAGAAACACGGAGCUGGGCCAUCGUCAGAACUAAGUCAGGGAAGGAGAUGGAUGAGAAGGCCAGAAUCAUUCCUAGUACAUUUGCUAACACUUUAUUGAGAAAUUGACCAUGAAUUAAUGGACUCAUCUUAAUUUCUUCUAAGUCCAUAUAUAGAUAGAUAUCUAUCUGUACAGAUUUCUAUUUAUCCAUAGAUAGGUAUCUAUACAUACACAUCUCAAGUGCAUCUAUUCCCACUCUCAUUAAUCCAUCAUGUUCCUAAAUUUUUGUAAUCUUACUGUAAAAAAAAGUGCACUGAACUUCAAAACAAAACAAAAAACAACAACAACAAAAAACAAGUCCAAACUGAUAUAUCCUAUAUUCUGUUAAAAUUCAAAAGUGAACGAAAGCAUUUAACUGGCCAGUUUUGAUUGCAAAUGCUGUAAAGAUAUAGAAUGAAGUCCUGUGAGGCCUUCCUAUCUCCAAGUCUAUGUAUUUUCUGGAGACCAAACCAGAUACCAGAUAAUCACAAAGAAAGCUUUUUUAAUAAGGCUUAAACCAAGACCUUGUCUAGAUAUUUUUAGUUUGUUGCCAAGGUAGCACUGUGAGAAAUCUCACUUGGAUGUUAUGUAAGGGGUGAGACACAACAGUCUGACUAUGAGUGAGGAAAAUAUCUGGGUCUUUUCGUCAGUUUGGUGCAUUUGCUGCUGCUGUUGCUACUGUUUGCCUCAAACGCUGUGUUUAAACAACGUUAAACUCUUAGCCUACAAGGUGGCUCUUAUGUACAUAGUUGUUAAUACAUCCAAUUAAUGAUGUCUGACAUGCUAUUUUUGUAGGGAGAAAAUAUGUGCUAAUGAUAUUUUGAGUUAAAAUAUCUUUUGGGGAGGAUUUGCUGAAAAGUUGCACUUUUGUUACAAUGCUUAUGCUUGGUACAAGCUUAUGCUGUCUUAAAUUAUUUUAAAAAAAUAAAUACUGUCUGUGAGAAACCAGCUGGUUUAGAAAAGUUUAGUAUGUGACGAUAAACUAGAAAUUACCUUUAUAUUCUAGUAUUUUCAGCACUCCAUAAAUUCUAUUACCUAAAUAUUGCCACACUAUUUUGUGAUUUAAAAAUUCUUACUAAGGAAUAAAAACUUUAAUAUACGAUAUGAUAUUGUCUAAUAAUUAAAAAAGACAUAAUGGAUGCUCAAUUAGUUUUAAGAUAUCUAUAACUAUAGGGAUACAAAUCACUACAGUUCUCAGAUUUACAGCUUUUUUUUGUCAUUGGCUUGAUGUCACACAUUUCCAAUCUCUUGCAAGCCUCCAGGCUCUGGCUUUGUCUACCUGCUCGUUCCCAAUGUAUCUUAAUGAAAAGUGCAAAAGAAAAACCUACCAA